GUUAUUUUCUUUUCUCCCCCAGCUGCCCCAGGGUUCUGGUUUCCCGAAUCACUUGGCAAAUAACCAGCAGGUGGGCAGAUGUCUUUUUUGCGUUCCUACGGACGCGUAGGCAAGUUCGAUGCGCCGGAGUGAACAGCCAGGGUCCCAUCUCUCAGCCGGCUCCCGGGCGGUGCUAGCAGGGAAGAGGGACGCGCCGGCGAAUGAAACACUACUAGCCCGGAAAGCCGCCCUGGACCUUCCACCCGGGCAGCGAGUCUGGCGGCCCCUCGCCGCCGCCCCCUCCGACCAGAACAGACUGCGCUGCGAGCCCCGGGCUUCCGCCGCAGCGCGCAGCAAUUGGAGGUGCCAGAGGAGACCAGCAGCAGCACUUGAUUUAGCUGGGCUGCGGGAAUUCCGACCUGUACACUUUCCAGAAGCCUGAUCUCUCCAAGUCCGCGCCCAGGGACUCGAGCCCCGGCUUCCAGGUUGACCCGAGCGCGCCCCCUUCGUGCUCUCGGCCGCGUUCACCGCGCGAGGCCUCCGGGUCCUGUUAAGCCCGAGCAGGUGAGCGACUGGGGGUGGUUCGGCGUCCGCCGAGACAGAGCCUGGCCCCGGGGGUCACCCUGGGGUGCUGCCUGGUACCUCCCAGGUACCCGCCUCCCGGAGCCCUAAGAGAGGCUGAAAACCACGGACGCUCCAGGACUCCGUUUUCUGUACUUUUGAGUAAUUUGCCAUCUUUUCCUUGCGCAAUUCGUACAAAGCCCUUCCGUGCUCACAAAGUUGAUGAUUGUGAAGAAGAAAAUGUAGGUUAGAGGAGAGGAAGCAGCAUCAGGACACCUUACCACCACUCACAGGCCGCUGCCUCAGCAUCCACCCCGCAGCCCACGUGUGGCAAGCCGGGGAAGGGGUGGAGUGAACGGCCGGAGACCACGUGGAGAAAGGGGCCGCUUUGGCCCUUCCAUCUGGGUGCCGGGAGCCCCUAGGCCCUCCGGCCAUGGCCGACAGCGGCGAUGCUGGCAGCUCCGGCCCCUGGUGGAAAUCGCUCACCAACAGCAGAAAGAAAAGCAAGGAAGCCGCAGUGGGGGUGCCGCCUCCCGCCCAGCCCGCUCCCGGGGAGCCCACGCCACCUGCGCCGCCCAGCCCGGACUGGACCAGCAGCUCCCGGGAGAACCAGCACCCCAAUCUCCUCGGGGGCGCCGGCGAGCCCCCCAAACCAGACAAGUUAUACGGGGACAAAUCCGGCAGCAGCCGCCGCAAUUUGAAGAUCUCGCGCUCCGGCCGCUUUAAGGAGAAGAGGAAAGUGCGCGCCACGCUGCUCCCGGAGGCGGGCAGGUCCCCGGAGGAGGCAGGCUUUCCUGGUGACCCCCACGAGGACAAGCAGUAGCCCCAAUAGCCUGCGCGCUCCAGGACUGCCUACCCAGCACUACCCCAAACCCCCAGUUCCAAACCCGAGACUUCAGGCCCGCCCCCUUACGCGUUGUCUCAUUCCACCAAAUUCAGAAUAUUUACACAAUGCCUUCAUGAUUUUAUUUUUCUGGAAAUUGAAGUGUCAAUUGGGUUCUCAAUAUUUCAUGACUCCAAGGAUGCAUUAAAUAUUUAUUUGUGGUAAGAGAAGAUACCUGCCGCGGAGGAGGGUGGCAUAAUUAUUUUUUUUUCAAAAAGCUAUUCUGGGGCCCUGGCCCCCUGGCUCCUGUCACAGCUCAGCUUGAACUCUGUAGCCUCUCAAAUGAAGAAGGUGGCUGUUAUUUAGGACUCUGUGGAAAGCAAAUCACAGUGCUGUUUUUAAUGCCUGAGAAAUGCACUUUAGGGGUAGACUUAUACCUUAAGUGAAGGAGUGGGGGAGGAAGAAGCAUUCUUAAGUAGAAGCAUUUUAAAAUAAGGCAGGAUUGCUUUUAAUGUUAAACUACAAAACUGUACAGCCUAUUUUAGUGUGGACUAUUAAAACCCUUGCACUGUAAGG